GCUGUUCUUCCGGGUUGGAGGCGCAGCGCCGCGGGGCCCAAGCCCGGGUCUGCCAGCGCGACGUCCUCUCGCGGCCCUCAGGGCACAGCCCAAGGCUGUCAGCCUCCCGGCCCAGGUGAGCGCGACGGCACUGGCGGGUGCGGGCAGCCGGGGCGCGCGCCUAGGGCGCAGCUGGGAAAGGGGCUCGGGCCUUUCCUGAAGACCACGGCCCUCGCCGGGAGAGAGACCUGUCAAAGAGCAAAGCGGGGCGGGGUCGGCGGUGUCCCGGGCGCAGGGUGCAUUGGGGUGUCCGCAGGCCGCAGGCUUAGGUGGGGAAGAAGCACCGUGCCUCUUGGUGUCCCUUUCUCGUCUCCUGCUGGGGCGAUGUCGAAGGGAGUGGGCUGGUGGAUUUGGGAACUGGGUCCCCGAAGAGGGCAGGGAAUGAGGCGGCAGCUGUGCAGGUGCAGAUAUUUGCAGCUUUGGGGGACAGCGAGAGUCGUACGGGGUCAUUUCGGCCCUCAAGAUCGGGGGUGGUGGAGAGGGAGGUCAUAGAGGACUUUCGAUGGGCGGUUCAUCCAGAGAGGUGGCAGCUGGAUGCCCUUGAGGUAUGCUUGACCCUUGAGGGAGUUCGGAGAGGGUGUCCGGCUGGGGACAUAGGAGAUUGCGAGCACAAAUUGUGAGUGUGAGUUGGGGCGGUCUGGCGGUGGUGGGUACAAGUUUCUGGGGCCUAGGCUGGUGAGGAGGAAGAGACAGCGGAGAGGGCGACCUGGGCAGAGCUAGUUCAAACUCAACAGCCGGAAUGACUAUUUGCAGCCGUGGCCAAUCGGCUUCCUAGGGAGGUUAUAAAUAGCGGUCUCGUGCAGAUGCCAGCGGGUGGCAGUUAGUUGCCGAGCAAGGGACGGCACCGGUGGCAGUAGCCGUGACACCAGUGGCUUUGGGUGAGGUCACGGCGCCUGCCAGCCGAAGCUGGCUCAGUAGGGUAUUGUGUCCUUGCUGGUAUGUCUCGCUUUUAAAAGCGUGACUUGUUUAUGGUUGCCGGUGUCCUUUAUUCACCCUGUGGCGCCGGCCAGUCCUUAGGUGGUCUGUUUGUCAGGAGUCUUGUAGGACAGACUUAUUCGGAGAAGCGCGUGGGGCUUAGGUGCCUACCUACUCUUCUUAUUUAAAGUGUGCCCCUUUUCUUCAUUGCACCCCUUUUAUUUGUAAACCUUGACUUUUUAUUAACAGACAGUUUAGGAUUGCCUUCUUUCCAGCAGGUGCGCUUAGGCUGCUUACCUUGGUGAUAGAAUCAGUUUUCCACAAGGCUACACAAACAUUUCCUUUUCAAAGGAAAUUUUCCGAAAAUCCUUGGAAAAUGUGCUCAAUAGGUACUUAGGCUUAAGGUCACCUAGCCCUAUUCAUUCAGUCAAAAAUACUGACUUCCUCUGUGUUGUGCAAAGCACUGGGGGAGAGUAAUACCAAAGUGAAUAUAACAGCUGAUAAGGAUAUUCUCAGUCCUGGCAACAACCCUGAGAGUGAUUUGCCUUCAAGGAAACUGGGGAGUCAGAAAAUUGGGAACUCAUAUCAACAUGGCAAACCUAUUGAAAACAGUGGUGACUGGCUGCUCGUGUCCUCUACUUAGCAAUUUGGGGUCCUGUAAGGGUCUACGUGUGAAGAAGGAUUUUUUACGAACAUUUUAUACUCACCAAGAACUGUGGUGUAAAGCGCCUGUAAAACCAGGAAUUCCAUAUAAGCAACUGACUGUUGGAGUCCCCAAAGAGAUAUUCCAAAAUGAGAAGCGAGUGGCAUUGUCUCCUGCUGGUGUUCAGAACUUGGUCAAGCAGGGUUUUAAUGUUGUCGUGGAAUCGGGUGCGGGCGAAGCUUCCAAGUUCUCAGAUGAUCACUAUAGAGUGGCAGGUGCCCAAAUCCAAGGGGCAAAGGAAGUGCUGGCUUCUGAUUUGGUGGUCAAAGUGCGAGCCCCUAUGGUUAAUCCAACAUUAGGUGUUCAUGAAGCUGACCUUUUAAAGACAUCAGGAACGCUGAUUAGUUUUAUUUACCCAGCCCAAAAUCCAGAGUUGCUAAAUAAACUUUCCCAAAGAAAAACUACAGUUCUGGCAAUGGACCAGGUUCCAAGAGUCACAAUUGCUCAGGGAUAUGAUGCGCUAAGCUCCAUGGCCAACAUUGCGGGUUAUAAGGCUGUUGUCCUAGCAGCAAAUCAUUUUGGACGUUUUUUUACUGGUCAGAUCACAGCUGCUGGAAAAGUUCCUCCAGCUAAGAUUCUGAUAGUUGGUGGUGGUGUUGCUGGGCUUGCUUCUGCAGGCGCAGCAAAGUCGAUGGGUGCAAUUGUUCGAGGAUUUGACACAAGAGCUGCAGCUUUGGAACAGUUCAAGUCUCUUGGUGCUGAGCCCUUGGAGGUGGACUUGAAGGAAUCUGGUGAGGGACAAGGAGGAUAUGCAAAAGAGAUGUCCAAAGAGUUCAUUGAAGCUGAAAUGAAACUCUUUGCUCAACAAUGCAAGGAGGUAGACAUCCUUAUCAGCACAGCACUUAUUCCAGGUAAAAAAGCUCCAGUUUUAUUUAAUAAAGAAAUGAUUGAGUCAAUGAAGGAAGGUUCAGUUGUUGUGGAUUUAGCUGCUGAGGCUGGUGGAAACUUUGAAACCACUAAGCCAGGAGAACUCUACAUUCAUAAGGGAAUUACUCACAUAGGCUACACAGACCUGCCCAGCCGAAUGGCCACUCAGGCCAGCACCCUAUAUUCCAACAACAUCACCAAACUCCUGAAGGCCAUCAGCCCGGACAAAGAUAAUUUUUAUUUUGAUGUGAAAGAUGACUUUGACUUUGGUACGAUGGGUCAUGUCAUUAGAGGAACUGUAGUGAUGAAAGAUGGUAAAGUGAUUUUCCCAGCUCCCACACCGAAAAAUAUUCCUCAAGGUGCCCCAGUAAAACAGAAGACAGUGGCUGAGCUGGAAGCUGAAAAAGCAGCUACCAUUACACCCUUCAGGAAGACAAUGUCAACGGCUUCUGCAUAUACAGCAGGUCUCACAGGGAUACUGGGUUUGGGCAUUGCGGCUCCCAAUCUAGCCUUUUCUCAGAUGGUGACCACUUUUGGCUUGGCUGGCAUUGUGGGGUAUCAUACCGUCUGGGGAGUGACCCCUGCUCUCCACUCACCACUGAUGUCUGUGACAAAUGCAAUCUCAGGGCUGACUGCAGUUGGUGGGUUGGCACUGAUGGGAGGACAUUUGUAUCCUUCCACAACUUCUCAGGGCCUUGCUGCUCUUGCUGCAUUCAUAUCCUCUGUCAACAUUGCAGGUGGCUUUCUGGUGACUCAGAGAAUGCUGGACAUGUUCAAGCGUCCCACUGACCCCCCAGAAUACAACUACCUGUACCUGCUCCCUGCCGGCACCUUUGUUGGUGGAUAUUUAGCUGCCCUCUACAGUGGUUAUAACAUUGAACAGAUCAUGUACCUAGGCUCGGGUUUGUGCUGUGUCGGUGCCUUGGCUGGCCUCUCCACCCAGGGAACAGCACGUCUUGGCAAUGCACUGGGCAUGAUUGGGGUUGCUGGAGGACUGGCAGCCACCCUCGGAGUCCUAAAACCGGGCCCAGAAUUACUAGCUCAGAUGUCUGGAGCGAUGGCUUUGGGUGGUACCAUUGGAUUGACAAUUGCCAAACGCAUCCAGAUUUCUGAUUUACCUCAAUUAGUUGCUGCUUUUCACAGUUUAGUGGGUUUGGCAGCUGUACUUACUUGCAUAGCUGAGUACAUUAUAGAAUAUCCACAUUUUGCUACGGAUGCAGCAGCAAAUCUCACCAAGAUUGUGGCCUACCUCGGCACUUACAUUGGUGGCGUCACCUUUAGUGGGUCUCUCAUUGCCUAUGGAAAAUUGCAGGGUCUCCUGAAAUCUGCCCCUCUCCUACUGCCUGGAAGGCACUUACUCAAUGCAGGCUUACUGGCUGCUAGUGUGGGCGGGAUAAUCCCAUUCAUGGUGGACCCAAGCUUUACUACUGGCAUCACCUGUCUGGGUUCAGUGUCUGCUCUCUCUGCUGUCAUGGGUGUGACUUUGACAGCUGCUAUUGGGGGUGCUGACAUGCCCGUCGUUAUCACUGUGCUGAACAGCUACUCAGGCUGGGCCCUGUGUGCAGAGGGCUUCCUGCUCAACAACAAUCUGCUGACCAUCGUGGGUGCACUCAUAGGCUCGUCUGGUGCUAUCCUGUCAUACAUCAUGUGUGUGGCAAUGAAUCGCUCCCUGGCUAAUGUGAUUCUUGGAGGCUAUGGCACCACUUCAACAGCUGGUGGAAAACCCAUGGAAAUUUCUGGCACACAUACGGAAAUCAACCUUGACAAUGCAAUUGACAUGAUUCGAGAAGCUAAUAGCAUUAUUAUUACACCAGGCUAUGGUCUCUGUGCAGCCAAAGCUCAAUACCCCAUUGCUGAUUUGGUAAAGAUGCUCACUGAGCAAGGCAAAAAAGUCAGGUUUGGAAUUCACCCAGUUGCAGGCCGAAUGCCUGGUCAGCUUAAUGUGCUGCUGGCUGAGGCUGGUGUGCCAUAUGACAUUGUGUUGGAAAUGGAUGAGAUCAACCAUGAUUUUCCAGAUACUGAUUUGGUCCUUGUAAUUGGAGCUAAUGACACUGUUAAUUCAGCAGCUCAAGAAGAUCCCAACUCUAUUAUUGCAGGCAUGCCAGUCCUUGAGGUCUGGAAAUCAAAGCAGGUGAUUGUUAUGAAGAGGUCUUUGGGUGUUGGCUAUGCUGCAGUGGACAAUCCAAUCUUCUACAAACCUAACACGGCCAUGCUUCUAGGUGAUGCCAAGAAAACAUGUGACGCGCUCCAGGCGAAAGUUAGAGAAUCCUAUCAGAAGUAAAUAUUAAGGAUCAAGCUGUUAGCUAAUAAUGCCACCUCUGCAGUUUUGGGAACAGGCAAAUAAAGUAUCAGUAUACAUGGUGAUGUACAUCUGUAGCAAAGCUCUUGGAGAAAAUGAAGACUGAAGAAAGCAAAGCAAAAACUGUAUAGAGAGAUUUUUCAAAAGCAGUAAUCCCUCAAUUUUAAAAAAGGAUUGAAAAUUCUAAAUGUCUUUCUGUGCAUAUUUUUUGUGUUAGGAAUCAAAAGUAUUUUAUAAAAGGAGAAAGAACAGCCUCAUUUUAGAUGUAGUCCUGUUGGAUUUUUUAUGCCUCCUCAGUAACCAGAAAUGUUUUAAAAAACUAAGUGUUUAGGAUUUCAAGACAACAUUAUACAUGGCUCUGAAAUAUCUGACACAAUGUAAACAUUGCAGGCACCUGCAUUUUAUGUUUUUUUUUUCAACAAAUGUGACUAAUUUGAAACUUUUAUGAACUUCUGAGCUGUCCCCUUGCAAUUCAACCGCAGUUUGAAUUAAUCAUAUCAAAUCAGUUUUAAUUUUUUAAAUUGUACUUCAGAGUCUAUAUUUCAAGGGCACAUUUUCUCACUACUAUUUUAAUACAUUAAAGGACUAAAUAAUCUUUCAGAGAUGCUGGAAACAAAUCAUUUGCUUUAUAUGUUUCAUUAGAAUACCAAUGAAACAUACAACUUGAAAAUUAGUAAUAGUAUUUUUGAAGAUCCCAUUUCUAAUUGGAGAUCUCUUUAAUUUCGAUCAACUUAUAAUGUGUAGUACUAUAUUAAGUGCACUUGAGUGGAAUUCAACAUUUGACUAAUAAAAUGAGUUCAUCAUGUUGGCAAGUGAUGUGGCAAUUAUCUCUGGUGACAAAAGAGUAAAAUCAAAUAUUUCUGCCUGUUACAAAUAUCAAGGAAGACCUGCUACUAUGAAAUAGAUGACAUUAAUCUGUCUUCACUGUUUAUAAUACGGAUGGAUUUUUUUUCAAAUCAGUGUGUGUUUUGAGGUCUUAUGUAAUUGAUGACAUUUGAGAGAAAUGGUGGCUUUUUUUAGCUACCUCUUUGUUCAUUUAAGCACCAGUAAAGAUCAUGUCUUUUUAUAGAAGUGUAGAUUUUCUUUGUGACUUUGCUAUCGUGCCUAAAGCUCUAAAUAUAGGUGAAUGUGUGAUGAAUACUCAGAUUAUUUGUCUCUCUAUAUAAUUAGUUUGGUACUAAGUUUCUCAAAAAAUUAUUAACACAUGAAAGACAAUCUCUAAACCAGAAAAAGAAGUAGUACAAAUUUUGUUACUGUAAUGCUCGCGUUUAGUGAGUUUAAAACACACAGUAUCUUUUGGUUUUAUAAUCAGUUUCUAUUUUGCUGUGCCUGAGAUUAAGAUCUGUGUAUGUGUGUGUGUGUGUGUGUGCGUUUGUGUGUUAAAGCAGAAAAGACUUUUUUAAAAGUUUUAAGUGAUAAAUGCAAUUUGUUAAUUGAUCUUAGAUCACUAGUAAACUCAGGGCUGAAUUAUACCAUGUAUAUUCUAUUAGAAGAAAGUAAACACCAUCUUUAUUCCUGCCCUUUUUCUUCUCUCAAAGUAGUUGUAGUUAUAUCUAGAAAGAAGCAAUUUUGAUUUCUUGAAAAGGUAGUUCCUGCACUCAGUUUAAACUAAAAAUAAUCAUACUUGGAUUUUAUUUAUUUUUGUCAUAGUAAAAAUUUUAAUUUAUAUAUAUUUUUAUUUAGUAUUAUCUUAUUCUUUGCUAUUUGCCAAUCCUUUGUCAUCAAUUGUGUUAAAUGAAUUGAAAAUUCAUGCCCUGUUCAUUUUAUUUUACUUUAUUGGUUAGGAUAUUUAAAGGAUUUUUGUAUAUAUAAUUUCUUAAAUUAAUAUUCCAAAAGGUUAGUGGACUUAGAUUAUAAAUUAUGGCAAAAAUCUAAAAACAACAAAAAUGAUUUUUAUACAUUCUAUUUCAUUAUUCCUCUUUUUCCAAUAAGUCAUACAAUUGGUAGAUAUGACUUAUUUUAUUUUUGUAUUAUUCACUAUAUCUUUAUGAUAUUUAAGUAUAAAUAAUUAAAAAAAUUUAUUGUACCUUAUAGUCUGUCACCAAAAAAAAAAAAUUAUCUGUAGGUAGUGAAAUGCUAAUGUUGAUUUGUCUUUAAGGGCUUGUUAACUAUCCUUUAUUUUCUCAUUUGUCUUAAAUUAGGAGUUUGUGUUUAAAUUACUCAUCUAAGCAAAAAAUGUAUAUAAAUCCCAUUACUGGGUAUAUACCCAAAGGAUUAUAAAUCAUGCUGCUAUAAAGACACAUGCACACGUAUGUUUAUUGCAGCACUAUUCACAAUAGCAAAGACUUGGAACCAACCCAAAUGUCCAUCAAUGAUAGACUUGAUUAAGAAAAUGUGCACAUAUACACCAUGGAAUACUAUGCAGCCAUAAAAAAGGAUGAGUUCAUGUCCUUUGUAGGGACAUGGAUAAAGCUGGAAACCAUCAUUCUGAGCAAACUAUUGCAAGGACAGAAAACCAAACACUGCAUGUUCUCACUCAUAGGUGGGAAUUGAACAAUGAGAACACUUGGACACAAGGUGGGGAACACCACACACCAGGGCCUGUCAUGGGGUGGGGGGAGUGGGGAGGGAUAGCAUUAGGAGAUAUACCUAAUGUAAAUGAUGAGUUAAUGGGUGCAGCACACCAACAUGGCACAUGUAUACAUAUGUAGCAAACCUGCACGUUGUGCACAUGUACCCUAGAACUUAAAGUAUAAUUAAAAAAAAAAAGAAAACAGAAGCUAUUUAUAAAGAAGUUAUUUGCUGAAAUAAAUGUGAUCUUUCCCAUUAAAAAAAUAAAGAAAUUUUGGGGUAAAAAAACACAAUAUAUUGUAUUCUUGAAAAAUUCUAAGAGAGUGGAUGUGAAGUGUUCUCACCACAAAAGUGAUAACUAAUUGAGGUAAUGCACAUAUUAAUUAGAAAGAUUUUGUCAUUCCACAAUGUAUAUAUACUUAAAAAUAUGUUAUACACAAUAAAUACAUACAUUAAAAAAUAA